ACGGCGACGGCGGCUGAGUGAGAACCUUGGCGGCUGUGGAGGCUGCCGCGGCUGCGAAGGAGGCGGCGGCGGUGGCGGAGGAAGAGGAGUGGCGGCAGCGGCGGCGGGGACCCGUGCGGGGAUGGCGGAGGUACCGCCUGGGCCUAGCAGCCUCCUCCCACCACCAGCACCUCCGGCCCCGGCGGCGGUCGAGCCCCGCUGUCCCUUCCCGGCGGGGGCCGCCCUCGCCUGCUGCAGCGAGGACGAGGAGGACGACGAAGAGCACGAAGGCGGCGGCAGCAGGAGCCCGGCGGGCGGAGAGUCGGCGACGGUGGCGGCCAAGGGGCAUCCGUGCCUCCGCUGCCCUCAGCCGCCGCAGGAGCAGCAGCAGCUCAACGGAUUGAUUAGCCCCGAACUGCGGCACCUCCGGGCGGCCGCCUCCCUCAAGAGCAAGGUCCUGAGCGUAGCAGAGGUGGCCGCGACCACAGCCACCCCUGACGGAGGCCCCAGAGCGACUGCAACAAAAGGAGCCGGGGUACACUCGGGCGAGAGGCCCCCUCACUCCCUCUCUAGUAAUGCAAGAACUGCGGUCCCCAGCCCGGUGGAGGCAGCGGCGGCGAGCGAUCCCGCGGCGGCCCGCAAUGGACUGGCCGAGGGCACCGAGCAGGAGGAGGAGGAGGAAGACGAGCAGGUGCGGCUGCUGUCUUCGUCCCUGACCGCCGACUGCAGCUUAAGAAGCCCUUCGGGCAGGGAGGUUGAGCCUGGGGAGGAUCGGACGAUACGAUAUGUCCGAUAUGAAUCCGAGCUACAAAUGCCCGAUAUCAUGAGACUGAUCACCAAAGAUCUGUCCGAACCCUACUCCAUUUAUACCUAUAGAUAUUUUAUCCACAACUGGCCACAGCUGUGCUUCUUGGCCAUGGUAGGGGAGGAGUGUGUAGGUGCCAUCGUUUGCAAGUUGGAUAUGCACAAAAAGAUGUUCCGCAGAGGUUAUAUAGCCAUGUUAGCCGUGGAUUCCAAAUACAGGAGAAAUGGCAUUGGUACUAACUUGGUUAAGAAAGCUAUAUAUGCCAUGGUUGAGGGAGACUGUGAUGAGGUUGUUUUGGAAACCGAAAUAACAAAUAAGUCCGCUUUGAAACUUUAUGAAAAUCUUGGUUUUGUUCGAGAUAAGAGGCUGUUCAGAUACUAUUUAAAUGGAGUUGAUGCACUGCGACUUAAACUGUGGCUGCGUUGAGAAACUGACAUCAAGGAACAACUAUCAUCCGCACAGAAUCGACCUUUGCAUGCAAUGCAAUUUGUACAGAAUUGCUUUGCAGGUGGAUUUAGUAAUUUCCAUGCAGCUCUUACCUGUCAGUGUCUCAUUGAGUGUCGCACAAUAUUUGUUGCACUUUGGCAUGGCACAUUUGUUCUGAAUUAAAAGAUUGUUUUAAACUUCAGGAGUUCUUUUGGUACCAACAAGAUGUGCCAGUUGAUAGCCAAGAUUUAUGUGUUCAUUUGCAAAGUCUGCUGACAAUGUUAUUUACACAGUGAUCAUUUUAUCACAGAACCAGUAAGUGGAACAUAAUUUUUGUUCCUUAAAAAAGCCAAUGUGGAUUGUAAAAGUCUUUAAGUAUACUAACAUUUCACACAAAACCUGCCCUAGUUUUCUGAAGUGGGUGAGGGAGACGCUUCAGUUUUAGGUUUUAUUUUUUCAAUAUUAAAUUUUCCAUUCUUGAAUAUUGGUACCUCAGUGAUUAGUGAAUGAAAAAAAUGUAGGGUGGGUAUGUCUUACAAUGAGUAAAGGUAACAAUUAAAUUUUGUCUGCCAGUGCCUGUGUAGAUAAGUAUAUUUGUCUUCAUCUCUAGUUUUUGAAUGCAUGCUAUCUUUUCCUUUUCUUUAAGGCCUUUGCAAGCAAACUUUUGUUUUUAUUUAAAUUCUAAAUUUGAUAAAUUAUUUCAGAUUUUUAUAAUUUGGAUACUUUUUUCAGGUGAAUGAAAGAAUGGUUUACUUUAGAAGUCCCUUUUUCCUUACAGUAACAAGUUGAAUCUACUUGGAAAAUUGAGAAAUGGCUCAAAAGAGAUAAGAAAAGUUGAUGGAGCCGGGAAUUGCUGGGGUUUAGAUGCACUUUUUCUUUUGAGAGUAAGGGAAGUUUUGGAAAAGAAUAGAAAAUUAGUGUAAGUUGAUAUGAUUUUAUUUAAUCAAAAUUACUGCUACGCUGCGAAGAACAGCUUUUACAAAGUAGCUGAAUUUGUUUUUCCCACUUGAUUUGGAUUCACAUUGCUUUCAUUUCUUAAAAUGCUUCACUUCAGGUUCUUGGUCUUGGAAAUAAAUUUCAAGGUGCAUUGUAUCCAUUUUAAGCUGCUUUAUUUUAUUUUCACUUGUAUGAGCAAAUUCUUGGGGGAGCUUUGCUUUUCUUCUGCCAGAAAAACAAAAGGGGGAAAUGAAAAUCUUUUUUGGAAUGAGUUCUGUGGGUUUUCUUAACAGCCACCAUGUUUAUUAGUUACAUUGUGUUUUGGCCAAUCAGUGCAAUGUAACAAAUUUUACAGUUAAUUGCUUUCAAUUGAGUCAGUAAACCUGUGAUAGAUAAUUUAUUUAACUGGAAAACCUAGGUACCCAUAAGAAAAAAGAUUCAUUCUCUGUGAAAACUGUAGGAAUCUGUUGUUGUUUUCAUUUGAAUAUGCUCUACUUCUGCUCUAGUAUUUGGUUUGGAAUAUAUUUUGUGGCUCUAAUUACUGUAUUUUUAAAAACCCUACCUCCAUUAACAGUUGGUAAAGGCCCCUUUUCAGGAAAGUUUGUUGCUUUUUUUUUUUUUUUAAAGGAAAGCUGCUCUUUGCUCAGUAUAGUGUUUUGAAAGUGAACAUAGUAACAAAUACUUUAAAAAUAAAGAUACACAAUUUAUAUUUGAAAAUAAAAACUUUCUGCUGGUGGGAUUAUUUAUAGUUCUUUAUUUUUAAAGAAAAUGUUUUCCUUUUUAUAUUGCUCUUGAAAGUUUAAUGAGCAGAAUACAAUACUGGUUAUAAUAAAAAUAUGGUAACCACACAGUACUCAGCCUUUCAAUAUGUUUUUGGUCAAACUUCAUUUAGGCACUAGCAUUUAGAAGAAUACCAAUCACAGUGAUGCUUUUGUUAUUUAAUAUGAAGGAAAUGGAACUAAAACAUUUAUGUCAUCAAAUUUUAUUUCACUUCUUUAUAUUUGACUUGCUGGUUGAUACAUAAUGGUUGAUGAACAUAUAUUUGCUUAAAUCACUAAUAGGGAUGGUUGUAAAGUAGAUAGAUCAUUGGUUCAACCAUUUUAGUGUUUUUGCCAGAUUGUCAAUGAAACCAUCAUACUGACCUUUUCCUCCAAAAUUGCCAAAUUGACUGAACUGGUUGGGUGUUUGUAAAGAUGACGUUAACUGUGUGACUAAAAAGUCAGAUGGUUGCCAUAUUGUUUGGAAUAUGUUGAAUGUCAGUGUAUGCCUUAUGUCUUUAAUUGGGUAUGCAAAAAAAUUUUUACUUAAGUAGAUUAAAAUUUUAACCUCUAGCAUGAAAACCCAGCACCAACACUGAAAGACUCCAUUCAGGUUGAAGUAGCCUCAAACAGUAAUUUACUUUUUGAUAAUAGGCUGUUGUUUUUCUUAAAUAAGCUUAAAACAAUUCUAUCUGAAAUUGGUAGCAUGGGUUCACUUGGCUACAACUGAGCAAAAUAGAUGCAACUUUCUUUUAAUGGGGUGCUGCCUCUUUAGGACUGACUGUACUAUCCACUGACACUGGUUUGGCAGUUGGUACUGCUGAACAUUUUUAUACAUGCUACCAUGAAGCUAUAUAUGUUAGUAUUGAAGAAGCUAACGGGUAUACUAUCAUUUUUGAUGUGUGGGCUGAUUAUAAUUUCCUGUAUUUCCUGUACAUUGGGAUGAAACUACUUUAGCAAAGUCCACAGAUCAGAAACCAGACGGUAGUUUUUGAAGUUGAAACCAGCAAAAUAAGAAAAAAUAAAAAAUCGAUUUUAAUAUUUUCUGCCUCUUUCCCAAAUUACCCUUCCCACUUGCUCGACAAAUCUAUGUAAAGCAGUUUGUUUUUUCAUGUUUUAACUUUACCUUGCCCUGUGUUAUGGUACUGGCUGACAUGUCUAAGACUGGAUGUGUAUAUUUAUUAUGGUGUCUAAAAAUCAUGAAGUUCAUCACUUUUCAGGAGUAUAGAUAAAAUCAAAUUGGUAGUACAUCAGAGUUACUUUUCAGUGCACCAUGACAUCACUAAAAUGAGUGCUGUAAUGUUACAGGGCUUUCAGGUUUGUAAAAACAUAACCAUAAAUUAUAUUGACGUCAGAUAUGAGUUGAGUAUCUAUAAAAUAUCACGUGUAUCUCAAAAUAUUGGACUGCUGUUUGACUGGAUAUUGCUGCAUAAUUUUCUUCUAUUGUCCCAUAUCCUUUUGGAGAGAGAUUUAAUGGGAUUUGAAAUGUGCAAGCUGUCUAAAUAAGAUGCAGUCAAAUAAAGUAUGGUUAAGUUGUGUUUGCAUUUUUCUUUUAGAUACAGCUGUGUGCAUUUUAUGAUUGGGUUGUUUUGCUUUUACCUACUAAGUAAAACAGCAACAAACAAUAUAUUGUUUCCCGCUUCCUGCCUUUCAUCUAAGAGUUACGGGGAAGAAGUAUUACAUAAUUGUCAUCACUGUUGUGUGUUCUGACAAAGUAAAUUUGAAAAUAACAUGAACUUGAUUUUUCUAAAAGUACUCAGUCAACUCAUAUGUCAGUUAUCGGUACAUUUUCCAUGUGUUCAGUCAAAAGUUUAUCUUUUUAGUCUGUUUCAUAGCAGUUUAUUUCUAAGACAGUUUUUAUUUUAAUUUACUUUUUUGUCUGUACACUGCCACUCUGUAAUGUUCCCCCCACCCCAUCCCACCCUUGGUAAGACACCAAAGUAAAAUAGAGCAAUAUCCAAAGAGCUUUUUGCCCCUGUCUUGUGAGGAGCUUUAAAUAGCUGUGAAUACUUCUGUAUGUCAAGAUUUUCGGAUUUUAGUGGAAGGAUGAAAUGAUCUGUUUUAAUCAUUUAACUGCUAAAUUACUUUUAUCAUGCAUGCCAAAUCUUUACAUUAUUCUUUAGAGUAAUACUGUAAAAGUAUCUGAGUUUGUUUUAUUUGGGCCUUAUGUGGAACUCGAAAUACUUCAUAAAUUCACUCUAAGGUCUAAAUAAGAACCAGAAGGUUGAUACCAUUUUUUCACACCAGUAAACACAGAUCAGUAUUAACCUGUAGCCCAGAGGUGUUAGAUUUAUUUUUUGAGACAGAGUCUCACUCUGUUGCCCAGGCUGGAGUGCGGUGGCACAAUCUUGGCUCACUGCAACCUCUGCCCCCUGGGUUCAAGCAAUUCUUGUGCCUUAGCCUCCUGAGUAGCUGGGACUACAGGUGCAUGCCACCACGCCCAGCCAAUUUCUUGUAUUCUUAGUAUGAGACAGGGUUUCACCAUGUUGGCCAGGCUGGUCUCAAACUCCUGACCUCAAGUGAUCUGCCCGCCUCGGCCUCCCAAAGUGUUGGAAUUACAGGCGUGAGCCACCACGCCCAGCCUAUGAUAUUCUUUUUAUAAGCAACUUUUAAAAAGUUUUUUAAAAGAUCUCAUAAGCAUAUAGCACUGCUACACUUUAGAUCACUACUGUCCAGUCACACUUUAUAUAAGGAUAGAUGUGUCCUUUUCACUCCCCAGUAUGGUAGUUACUAGUCACAUGUGUAGCUACUGAGCCCCUGAAGUGUGGGUGGGAUGAUUGAGCUGAAUUUGUAAUUUUAAUCAAAGUUAGCCACAUGUGGCUUGUGGCUACUGUAUUGGACAGCAGAGCUUUAGAUAAGCAGUAAUAACAGGAAGGGAGUGUUUGUAUAGGUUGAAAGAUAAAAUGGAAGGAUCACAAUUAGGCCAGAUGUGGUGGCUCACGCCUAUUAUCCCAGCGUUUUGGGAGGCUGAGAUGGUAGUUUGCAACCAGCCAGGACAGCAUAGCAAGACUGUUUCUGAAAAAUCUUUUAAAAUAACACAACUAAAAAUUACCUCUGAGCAAGAGUAUAGCUGAACUGUUUAUACUGACAAUAUAUUUCAUUAAUACAGUGUUUGACCACUUUCCACCCCACCAACCACUGCCCUUGUUAUGUAGCCUUUCUGAGAAAAGCAGCCCUUUCAGAUUUUAUUGUUGGAAGUUCCUUGGGUUGCAGAGAUGCAGAUUCAAGUGCCAAAAGUUGUUUCUGAUGAGACUUACCUUUUUAGCCUUAAAAUAUUUGUAUAGUUGGCUCUAAUAAUUUCUCAUUUUUGAUGAAUUUGAAAUCAUUUCACUUCUAAAUGAGAUUGGUCAUCUCAUGAGUGGUCAAGUUGGAACAUGGAGGUCUAUCAUGUUUUUAACCUCCAAGAUCCACUUAUGGGGAUGAGGCCAAAGGCCAAUGUUACUUCUAGAAGAACCAGAUUAAUUUUUCUGCCUUCCAUCACCGCAGUGUAUUACCUUUGACCCUCGCUGGUCAUCUGGUAAGUGUAGUUCAUCAAAAGAGCAGAAAUAGGCAUAGUAAACACCUGGACACAAAGACAGUGCCAGGCUUGGUACAACCUGUUAACACUGUUGAGGAAAGAGCUCAAAACAUGCAUUACUUUGGGGAUUAAGUCAGUGUUUAAUCUCAAUAUGAAACAGACCUAGAAAUAACAAAGACCACUGAAGUGCCAAAUUUAUCUUCUAAUACUACUAUUUAAACUAUGCAAUAUGGGGGUUAUAAUGAAAUAGUUUUAGUCUAUGUAAGGUUUUUAUAAUGCUAAGAAAUAAGCUUAUUUUUAGAUAUGGAUUUUUUAUGACUACCUCUUUGCUGUAUGAAUAUCUUAAUUUUCUAAUACCUCAGUUUCAUGAGAACUGUAUGUACAUUUUUGUAAAUAAAAUAAUUUACCAUAUACUAGGAGAAGGACCUGCUUUUAAAGAAAUUGUGUAAAGACAUUUGUUAUUGGAUGUGUUACAUAGUAAAUCAAUUUGAAAUUUCUUAAAAACGUUUAUAAGACUUUUCUGGUCUCCUUGACCGAGGGAUUUUAGUAUAAGUAUUUAGUGAGAUUUGUAUUCUAGGAAGUGUGUGCCGUCACUUGUUCAUUUACAACUGCAAAGAUUGUAUGUCUCCUAUGUUUUCCUUUCAUGCCAAAGAAACUCACCCUUUUUAAAAGCCAGCAGGUUGCACAAACCAAAAACAAAAUAUUUUGCCCCUUAAAUAGGCAUUUUAAGAAGUUUUAUUUCCUGGUACUUAAAUAUUGUGUAGAGGGAAAGCUAGUUGUAAUAAUUUGUAAAAAUGCGUGUAUUUUUAGGAAUGCGCUAUUUCCAGUAAGGGAAGUAUUGACAUUUUUAAGGAACUGUGCUGCAUUAAAAUCCACAGUUGCAUGAAACUUUUAAAAGUUUAAGAUAUAAAGUAAUUGCUAAAAUUUGUGAACUACUCAGAGGACUCAAUGCCCUAACAUGUAGGGGAUUGAUCAUUGCGAUGUUUAGGCCAGGAUUUCUCAUGAUUGUAUAUGGUUAUUGAUCAUUUUUAAGGGGCUGAACCUGCUGCCUUUAUACUUUUGACACCUCCCUCCCUCCCUCCCUCCAAACUGUGGCUGUAAACAGUGACUCUGCAUAGUCAGCGUUAUACUUGAUUUCUUUGUGAAUGCAAAUAAAAUAAAAUUUGUAAGUCCACCAAA